CAGCUCAUUCAAGGUCACGGAGGGAGGAAGAGGUGCUGCUGGGAUUUGAACCGAGACCCAAGUCCAAGUCCAGGCCCAAGUCCAGGCCCGUCUUCACCAUCCGGGGAGCUCUCUGCCCGGCCCCAGCCCGAGGAGGCCCACACUAAUCCAGCCACAGCCUUGCCCAUGGGGGGCUGUUCUCGGAGGAGGGCGAGAGCUGCCCUUGCCCCGGGGGUGACUGUUGGCAGCCCCAGGCGUGUAGCCCGGCAAGGCCUGGACACAGGGCAGGGCUGAGCCGUGCCCAGUGGGGACCACAGCAGGCGGGCCAGCUUCUGCCCAGCGGGAGGAGGAGAACCUUCCAGGUGCACCAUCUCGGGAGGCACCUCGGUCCCGCCAGAGCAGACGUAAGCGGGAGCUGGCUGUGAGGGGACCACAGCUUAGAACAGGACCCCAAAAGAUGGGCUCUGAGGUCCCUGCAGCCAAGAGCCAGGAUUCUGGAGCAUCAUGGAGCAGUUUAACCCCGCCCUGGAGAACCUGGUGUACCUGGGCAACAACUACCUGCGUGCCUUCCACGCUCUGUCCGAGGCGGCCGAGGUCUACUUCAGUGCCAUCCAGAAGAUUGGGGAGCGUGCCCUGCAGAGCCCCACCUCACAGAUUCUGGGGGAGAUCUUGGUGCAGAUGUCUGACACCCAGCGGCACUUGAACUCUGACCUGGAGGUGGUGGUGCAGACAUUCCAUGGAGGCCUGCUGCAGCACAUGGAGAAGAACACCAAGCUGGACAUGCAGUUCAUCAAAGACAGCCGCCAGCACUAUGAGCUCGAGUACCGCCACCGAGCGGCCAACCUGGAGAAGUGCAUGUCUGAGCUGUGGCGCAUGGAGCGCAAGAGAGACAAGAACGUGCGGGAGAUGAAGGAGAGUGUGAACCGGCUGCACGCACAGAUGCAGGCCUUCGUGUCUGAGAGUCAGCGGGCGGCUGAAUUGGAAGAGAAGCGGCGCUAUCGCUUCCUAGCAGAGAAGCACCUGCUACUUUCCAACACCUUCCUGCAGUUCUUCGGCCGGGCCCGGGGGAUGCUCCAGAACCGCGUGCUGCUGUGGAAGGAGCAGUCUGAGGCCAGCCGCAGCCCGUCGCGCGCCCACUCCCCCGGCCUGCUGGGCCCCGCGCUGGGGCCGCCCUACCCCUCGGGCCGCCUGACGCCCACCUGCCUGGACAUGCCCCCGAGGCCCCUGGGAGAGUUCAGCUCCCCCCGCAGCCGGCACGGCUCCGGCUCCUACGGCACCGAGCCCGACGCGAGGCCCGCGUCCCAGCUAGAGCCAGACCGUCGCUCCCUGCCCCGCACGCCGUCGGCCUCCUCGCUCUACAGCGGCAGCGCCCAAAGCUCGCGCUCCAACUCCUUUGGCGAGCGCCCGGGCGGCGGCGGGGGCGCCAGGAGAGUCCGCGCCCUGGUCUCCCACUCGGAGGGCGCCAACCACACGCUGCUGCGCUUCUCCGCUGGGGACGUGGUGGAGGUGUUGGUGCCCGAGGCCCAGAACGGCUGGCUCUACGGCAAGCUGGAGGGCUCGUCCGCGAGCGGUUGGUUCCCCGAGGCGUACGUGAAGGCUCUGGAGGAGGGGCCCGUGAAUCCCAUGACCCCCGUGACCCCCAUGACCUCCAUGACCUCCAUGUCCCCCAUGACACCCAUGAACCCCGGGAACGAGCUGCCUUCCAGGUCCUACCCACUCCGGGGCAGCCACAGCCUCGAUGACCUCCUGGACCGGCCGGGCAACUCCAUAGCACCCUCGGAGUACUGGGAUGGCCAGUCCCGCUCCCGCACCCCAAGCCGGGUGCCAAGCCGUGCCCCCAGCCCUGCACCUCCACCCUUGCCCAGCAGCCGCCGCAGCAGCAUGGGCAGCACAGCAGUUGCCACUGACGUCAAGAAACUGAUGUCCUCAGAGCAGUACCCACCACAGGAGCUCUUCCCGAGGGGCACAAAUCCUUUUGCCACUGUCAAGCUUCGUCCCACCAUCACCAAUGACCGCUCAGCACCCCUCAUCCGCUGAGGCGGGGUCCGAGGUCGUACCCCACAGUGCACCUGCCCAGGGGCUGUUCAGAGCUGGCAAUGGCAGCGACAGCAGCAACAGCAGCAGAUCCAAGAAGCGGGUCCCUGAGACGGGGGGUGGCUGCCCUCCCCAGACCACCCCGGCAGCCUGAGCAGCUCCAAAGCACUGGCUUGGGGUCCGAGACCUUCAAAGUAAAGCAGGCGGAAUGGGGGGACAGGACAAUUUCUCCCCCUCCAGGGGCUCCAGGACUCUCCCUGGGGGGCCCACCUCUUGCCCCCUAACCUCUUUCCCCCUUUUCUGCCCCCGUGGGGAGGAGCCCCUUGUACCUGCUCCGUGCCCAACACAUGCCCUCUCUGUACAUCUUUUGUAAAUGAUGAGAAAUAAAGGAAGUGGACGCAAA